GCUGGCUGGAACAGCCUGAGCUCUGUUCUGGGACCCCGCUUUACUGAAAUAAGAUAACCUUCAAUGUUUUAGCCCAGCAAAUCUCAUUGCCCCACAGCAUAAAACCAAGGUUGAGAGGCUUUCUGGGGUCCCUCAGCUGAUACAAGUGGGGUAUGCAUGGAGGACACUCCAUCUAUCCUGGGCAAAUUUCUUGAGCCUUGCAGACUGGCUUACAAUGUGUCACGGGCUUCUGUUGUCUUGCUGCCUAUCUGUAAGUAGUAAAAAGUCUCUUCAUGCAGCUUGUUGUAUGCACAGGUGUUUUCUCUCACUGGACUCAGACAAGUUGGUGACCCGCACACAAUAAACCUGCUCCACAACAAGAGGAGAAGGAAUUCCAGAGCUCAAAAUGGAGAAAGGAACAGAGUAAGAACAAUGGCUUCAGGAGGAAAAUGCAAUGAUAGAAGCUUUGAAAGAAAGACAACUAGAAUUCAGGUCAUAGUAGAUGAUGAUACCUGCCUGUCUGACCUUUGAGGAAGGGGAAUUUCUGAAACCUAAGGCUUCCUUGUAUUGCUCAAUUCAGUGAGAAAGAAAUCACUAAUGAUAGCAGGGUUUUGCUCUGUCGCCCCCGCUGGAGCGCAGUGGCACAAACAGAGUACAUUGCUGUCUAUCUUCUGGACUCAAGUGAUCUUCCCUCCUCAGCCUUCUGAGUAGCUGGGACUACAGAUGCAGAUAGAAAUAUUAGUUUUAUGAGAAACUAUUUCUUAAAGGAUGAAACAUUCCACAAAAUAUAUUUUAUCACAGACUAUGGGUGGAUUCCACUGGGAGAAAAGAGGAUCUAAAUGCCAGGCUCACCCCUCACAUUCUAUUCAACUGCACAGGAUAGAAUGAUAAAGCCUGUUGUGUCCACCAUCUCCAAAGGAGGUUACCUGCAGGGAAAUGUUAACGGGAGGCUGCCUUCCCUGGGCAACAAGGAGCCACCUGGGCAGGAGAAAGUGCAGCUGAAGAGGAAAGUCACUUUACUGAGGGGAGUCUCCAUUAUCAUUGGCACCAUCAUUGGAGCAGGAAUCUUCAUCUCUCCUAAGGGCGUGCUCCAGAACACGGGCAGCGUGGGCAUGUCUCUGACCAUCUGGACGGUGUGUGGGGUCCUGUCACUAUUUGGAGCUUUGUCUUAUGCUGAAUUGGGAACAACUAUAAAGAAAUCUGGAGGUCAUUACACAUAUAUUUUGGAAGUCUUUGGUCCAUUACCAGCUUUUGUACGAGUCUGGGUGGAACUCCUCAUAAUACGCCCUGCAGCUACUGCUGUGAUAUCCCUGGCAUUUGGACGCUACAUUCUGGAACCAUUUUUUAUUCAAUGUGAAAUCCCUGAACUUGCGAUCAAGCUCAUUACAGCUGUGGGCAUAACUGUAGUGAUGGUCCUAAAUAGCAUGAGUGUCAGCUGGAGCGCCCGGAUCCAGAUUUUCUUAACCUUUUGCAAGCUCACAGCAAUUCUGAUAAUUAUAGUCCCUGGAGUUAUGCAGCUAAUUAAAGGUCAAACGCAGAACUUUAAAGACGCCUUUUCAGGAAGAGAUUCAAGUAUUACGCGGUUGCCACUGGCUUUUUAUUAUGGAAUGUAUGCAUAUGCUGGCUGGUUUUACCUCAACUUUGUUACUGAAGAAGUAGAAAACCCUGAAAAAACCAUUCCCCUUGCAAUAUGUAUAUCCAUGGCCAUUGUCACCAUUGGCUAUGUGCUGACAAAUGUGGCCUACUUUACGACCAUUAAUGCUGAGGAGCUGCUGCUUUCAAAUGCAGUGGCAGUGACCUUUUCUGAGCGGCUACUGGGAAAUUUCUCAUUAGCAGUUCCGAUCUUUGUUGCCCUCUCCUGCUUUGGCUCCAUGAACGGUGGUGUGUUUGCUGUCUCCAGGUUAUUCUAUGUUGCGUCUCGAGAGGGUCACCUUCCAGAAAUCCUCUCCAUGAUUCAUGUCCGCAAGCACACUCCUCUACCAGCUGUUAUUGUUUUGCACCCUUUGACAAUGAUAAUGCUCUUCUCUGGAGACCUCGACAGUCUUUUGAAUUUCCUCAGUUUUGCCAGGUGGCUUUUUAUUGGGCUGGCAGUUGCUGGGCUGAUUUAUCUUCGAUACAAAUGCCCAGAUAUGCAUCGUCCUUUCAAGGUGCCACUGUUCAUCCCAGCUUUGUUUUCCUUCACAUGCCUCUUCAUGGUUGCCCUUUCCCUCUAUUCGGACCCAUUUAGUACAGGGAUUGGCUUCGUCAUCACUCUGACUGGAGUCCCUGCGUAUUAUCUCUUUAUUAUAUGGGACAAGAAACCCAGGUGGUUUAGAAUAAUGUCGGAGAAAAUAACCAGAACAUUACAAAUAAUACUGGAAGUUGUACCAGAAGAAGAUAAGUUAUGAACUAAUGGACUUGAGAUCUUGGCAAUCUGCCCAAGGGGAGACACAAAAUAGGGAUUUUUACUUCAUUUUCUGAAAGUCUAGAGAAUUACAACUUUGGUGAUAAACAAAAGGAGUCAGUUAUUUUUAUUCAUAUAUUUUAGCAUAUUCGAACUAAUUUCUAAGAAAUUUAGUUAUAACUCUAUGUAGUUAUAGAAAGUGAAUAUGCAGUUAUUCUAUGAGUCGCACAAUUCUUGAGUCUCUGAUACCUACCUAUUGGGGUUAGGAGAAAAGACUAGACAAUUACUAUGUGGUCAUUCUCUACAACAUAUGUUAGCACGGCAAAGAACCUUCAAAUUGAAGACUGAGAUUUUUCUGUAUAUAUGGGUUUUGUAAAGAUGGUUUUACACACUAUAGAUGUCUAUACUGUGAAAAGUGUUUUCAAUUCUGAAAAAAAGCAUACAUCAUGAUUAUGGCAAAGAGGAGAGAAAGAAAUUUAUUUUACAUUGACAUUGCAUUGCUUCCCCUUAGAUACCAAUUUAGAUAACAAACACUCAUGCUUUAAUGGAUUAUACCCAGAGCACUUUGAACAAAGGUCAGUGGGGAUUGUUGAAUACAUUAAAGAAGAGUUUCUAGGGGCUACUGUUUAUGAGACACAUCCAGGAGUUAUGUUUAAGUAAAAAUCCUUGAGAAUUUAUUAUGUCAGAUGUUUUUUCAUUCAUUAUCAGGAAGUUUUAGUUAUCUGUCAUUUUUUUUUUUCACAUCAGUUUGAUCAGGAAAGUGUAUAACACAUCUUAGAGCAAGAGUUAGUUUGGUAUUAAAUCCUCAUUAGAACAACCACCUGUUUCACUAAUAACUUACCCCUGAUGAGUCUAUCUAAACAUAUGCAUUUUAAGCCUUCAAAUUACAUUAUCAACAUGAGAGAAAUCACCAACAAAGAAGAUGUUCAAAAUAAUAGUCCCAUAUCUGUAAUCAUAUCUACAUGCAAUGUUAGUAAUUCUGAAGUUUUUUAAAUUUAUGGCUAUUUUUACACGAUGAUGAAUUUUGACAGUUUGUGCAUUUUCUUUAUACAUUUUAUAUUCUUCUGUUAAAAUAUCUCUUCAGAUGAAACUGUCCAGAUUAAUUAGGAAAAGGCAUAUAUUAACAUAAAAAUUGCAAAAGAAAUGUCGCUGUAAAUAAGAUUUACAACUGAUGUUUCUAGAAAAUUUCCACUUCUAUAUCUAGGCUUUGUCAGUAAUUUCCACACCUUAAUUAUCAUUCAACUUGCAAAAGAGACAACUGAUAAGAAGAAAAUUGAAAUGAGAAUCUGUGGAUAAGUGUUUGUGUUCAGAAGAUGUUGUUUUGCCAGUAUUAGAAAAUACUGUGAGCCGGGCAUGGUGGCUUACAUCUGUAAUCCCAGCACUUUGGGAGGCUGAGGGGGUGGAUCACCUGAGGUCGGGAGUUCUAGACCAGCCUGACCAACAUGGAGAAACCCCAUCUCUACUAAAAAUACAAAAUUAGCUGGGCAUGGUGGCACAUGCUGGUAAUCUCAGCUAUUGAGGAGGCUGAGGCAGGAGAAUUGCUUGAACCCGGGAGGCGGAGGUUGCAGUGAGCCAAGAUUGCACCACUGUACUCCAGCCUGGGUGACAAAGUCAGACUCCAUCUCCAAAAAAAAAAGAUUAUAUAUAUAUAUAUAUGUGUGUGUAUGUGUGUGUGUGUGUGUGUGUGUAUAUAUAUAUAUAUAUAUAUACACACACACACACACACUUUUUAUAUAUAUAUAUAUAUAUAUAUAGUGGAACUUACAAAUGAGAGUAAUAUAAUGAUGAAAUUUUGAACUGUUAUUUAUAAACAUCUAAGGUAAAAUGGUUAGUCAUGGCCAGAGUAUGUUUCAUCCUUUAAUUUUUGUCCAUUUGAAAAUAAGGAUUUUUGAAAGAAUUAUACCAAUUAAAAUUAUUAAAGGCAAACAUAGAAUUCAUAAAAAAUUGUCCAAAGUAGAAAUGAUGACCUAUAAUUUGGAGCAUUUCCAAUUCAGUAAUUUCAAUUUUGCUCUUGAAAACAUUUAAUAUAUAUCCAAGACUGACAUUUCUUUAGCUGAACCUAACGUUUGGGUCUCUGAGUGAAUUUAUAAUAACUCCUUCCUUCCUUAGCAUAGGGUUUUCAAAAUUUGAUUUAUAAUUCCUAUUUCCAGUAAAUAUUGUUCAUUUGUCCACAUCUCUCCCUAUGAUAUGUUGCUGGAGGUAAGAAUUUCUUUCAUAUUCCUAUUUUUUUUUUCCCCAUAGACUAGGCUCAUAGAAUUUAAACAAGCAAAUUUUCCUGAGCUUUUUCUUGCCAAAUGAAAGAAGACUGGUAAAUUCUCAUAGAGAGGUUUGUGUAGUUCUUGGCUCUUCCUGGGGUUAAUGUGCUUAUAUUCACAGUGGCAAAUUGGUCUCAGACUUUAAUUUAUUUAUUUUUGAUUUGAAUUUCUCUUUAAAAGUAUCAAUUUAAAAGGUAACUAGAAUUAUUCUUUCUCAUUUUCAAAAGUGAUUUUUGCAUUAUUAAAUUUCCCUGCCAUUGUAAUGCCAUUUCACGCAGAAAAAAAGUCAGCCAGUAAUUAAGAAAAAAAGUGAUGGAGAUUAAGUAGUAUUUUGGCUUAUUUUUAGGACUCAUCAUGAGAAGACACAGUUCCUUUAAUCAGGAAAUUAAUAUCCAUAAUUUUCACUCAAAAUUGCAGUAUGUAAAGCAGAUUCUCAAAAACUCUCCUGAACACUUAUUUAUAUAUAUGUUUUUAUAUAAGUAAAAUUUUUCUCAUAUUUUUAUACGAUAUGCACACACACACAUACAUGCACAUACUACUUACUACAUGUUCUGUACUUGUACUUUGUACCAUGCAUAUUCAAAUGUUUAUAUACAUAAGUUUAUUAUAACAUAAACAGUAAAAGUAAUGAAUACUGUUUAAAAUAACUAAUAUAGUAUUUUUUAAUUUUUGUGGGGAUGGAUUCUCAAAUACUUGUGAUUUUAAAAGAUUCUAAAGCUAAAACACAACUUGAUUUUAAAAAGAAUGAUUCUCCUUACACAAUUAUAAAUAUUUGCAGUAAAUAUUUUCCUUAUAAUACUGUUUUGACCCCAUUUAAAAAGUAUUAGAUUAUAUUCCUUUGAUCCAAUGAAAACUGAACCUUAUAAAUGGUUAGCUGAAAGUAGACCUUAUUCUUGUCCUUCUUUAGAAGAGUAAAGAUUUGUCCUAGGGAAGAUGGCUGACUUCGGUUCCCAACAUGCGUAUGCAUUUAGACUGUAGCUCCUCAGCCCUGUGGACACAAAAUUUGGACAGCUUAUUAGGUUACGUUAGCAAUGCAUGACGGUUUCUCCAACACUAAGAUAUUCACGUUGAAACAGAUUUCCUGUUCGUCUUAUGUGUCUGGUAAAAUUGUUUCCCCAAUUACAAUUUGACAUAUCAAUAGAGGGUUAACAAGAGUAUAAUUACAUAACAGAAUUCCUCAUGAACUGUAAUCAGUCUACAGGAAAAUCAUUAUUUUAUCUUGAUUUGCAGAUGAAUAUACUGCUAAGAAAGGGAGCAACUCUGACCUUUGUUAAAGUUGAUCUUUUGUAAUUGAGGUAUAAGGUAUGAAAAGAUAAAAAACCGAAGGCCAGAGAAUCAGGAAAUGAAAGAUAGUAUGGACUGAAGGUAACAAUAUUUUAAUGUUAUGCAAUAUAGUCAGAGAAAUAUUAAAAAUUAGUUGUUUGCUGUGCAUAGGUGGAUCUCGCAGGAAGCUAAUGAAACCUAAGCUUCAGUGCCUCUCACUUAGACAUGUUCCAUUCGAGGUCCUGAACCUAACUUUGUAUUAGGAAUUCUGUACUAAUUUUGUUGAAGAAGACCAGCAAAGUUGUGUACACUUCUACCCCCACAAAAUCUGCAUUGUCCAUGUGAGUAAAGUAAAAUAAUUCCUGUUAUUUUUUUCUGUUAGAAAUAAGUAUGGAGGAUAUGUUUUUAAAAAUUUAUGAGUUAAUUGAAAUAUCCAUAUAUAACAAGUGACUUUCUCACAAUAUAUAUGAUGUGAUAUAUAGGGAGAUAGUUUCACUUUCAUCAUAUUUUAUACGUUGAUUCUGAACUAUAGAAAAAUAAUAAAUGGGAUUUUAAUUAUAGCUCUUAGUUGGGAAAGAAAUAUAGAGAGAUGUGGGAUUUGAAUGCCCAUGAAAGACAUUUUAUUUUACUUGAAUAUAUUCUUGCUUCACUUUACCCUCCAUAAUAUGUUGUACAUUAGUGCUGAUCAAGUUUACAGAGUUACAUUUUGCUUUCCUAACCAUUCAGUCAGGAAUUAAAAUAUGGCAUUGUAUAACAACUGGGAAGAAGCUCAUAGUGGAUAUAAAUUAGAGUAGAUAAUGGGUCACCUUGAUAGCCUCUGUUUACAUUACUUGUAUAUGGGCAAAAUAAUUAUUACCUAUACGUGUAUUUAAGCUUAAUUUUCAUAUAAACAGUAUUUUUAAUCUAUGUUAAAAUAGAUAAUAUCUAAAAGUGUGAUCUCUAGGUAGUCCUUAGUUUAUUAGUACUGUACUUCAAAAAGAUUUUUAAAUAGGUCCGGCACGGUGGCUCAUGCCUGUAAUCCCAGCACUUUGGGAGGCUGAGGCGGGCGAAUCACCUGAGGUCAGGAGUUCGAGAUCAGCCUGGCCAACAUGGUGAAACCCUGUCUCAACUAAAAAUAUAAAAAUUAGCCGGGCGUGGUGGCAGGCGCCUGUAAUCCCAGCUACUCGGGAGGCUGAGGCAGGAGAAUCACUUGAACCCAAGGGGCAGAAGCUGCAGUUAGCCAAGAUCGCAUCAUUGCACUCCAGCCUAGGGGACAAGAGCGCGAGACUUCAUCUCAAAAAAAAAAAAAAAAAAAAAAAAAGAUUUUUAAAUAAUAGCUAAAGGUAUGCUCUCUAGGUCAUCCUUAGUUUAUUAGUACUGUACUUAAAAAUUAUUUUUUAAUAGUCAAUUUUGGGAGAUAAUUAUUUCUUUCCUUAUAUUUUCCAAUUAGUUGGUGUCUAAAAAUAAAUGUUUUGUCUAAUUUUAGAUCAGGUAUACAUUCACAAAAGCAUAAAUCAUAGUCUCACAGGAAAUUCACCAAUUUUCCAUAUGUCGUGAGAUAACUGUCCUUUCUACAACCUCAUAACAAUGAAUUUAUAUAAUUACCUAGAUUUUCUUAGUGUGAAUCUACCCAUUAGUUUUAUUUUCUUGGUAGUUAUUUUUUUCCCUCCUCUCUGUUACUAUUGGCCUUAAAAUACACAGAGGACGGUUACAGUGUCCUAAUAGCUGUUACAUGUGUGUGUUUCAGCGUACUUGAAUCAAGUGUACAUUUAUAGUACCAAUAACCGCCUUUACAGCUUUACAGUUAACAAUUCUCUCACAAAACUGUAGAGCAUUAGGCAUCUGAGAGCCAUAGAGGGCCAACUUUGUUCCAGAGUGAACAUGCUUUUUUUCCUCAACAUAUACACUACUGAUUUUUUUUAAAAGUAUGACUUUCAAGUGAAUUAAUGUAUUGGUUAGGAGAACUGCUUGCUAAGUCCUUAUUACCUCUUGUUAAAGCCUCAGAAGGCCGUGCUGAAAGCCAGAGGGGAAAAAAAGAGUAAUGCACAGGUAUCUCUUUUGCAGUGGUGACUGUAUUUUGAGUACCUUGUGUGACAGGGUAUUAUUACAGCAUCUUGUGGGAAAACCUAUUAGGCCUUUGCAUGUUAAAGCUGUAUAAUUUGUUGGGUUGUGAGUGGUCUGACUUAAAUGUGUAUUAUAAAAUUUAGACAUCAAAUUUUCCUACUAACUAACUUUAUUAGAUGCAUACUUGGAAGCACAGUCAUAUCACACUGGGAGGCAAUGCAAUGUGGUUACCUGGUCCUAGGUUUGAACUGUCUUAUUUCAAAAGAUUUCUGAAUUAAUUUUUCCCUAGAAUUUCUCCUUCAUUCCAAAGUACAAACAUACUUUGAAGAAUGAAACAGAUUGUUCCCAUGAAUGUAUGCUCAUACUCGACUAGAAACGAUCUAUGUUAAAUGACUGUGUAUAUGAAUUAUUUCAAGUACUACCCCAAAUAACUUUCUUAUUGCUCUGAAAGAAGAAAAGCAAUGUAAAUCACUAUGAUUAUUGCACAAACAACCAGAAUUCUCCAACAAUUUUAAGUAAUCUGAUCCUCUUCUUGGAGAAAAUUGUUACCUAAUAGUUUUUCCUUAUGAAUGUUAUUACUACUGGUAUAAAUCAAAUUUCUAUAAAUUUCCUACUUAAGUCUUAAGAACUGGGUUCUUCCUUUGAUGUUAUUCAUGUUCAGAAAGGAAACAACACUUUACUCUUUUAGGACAAUUCCUAGAAUCUAUAGUAGUAUCAGGAUAUAUUUUGCUUUAAAAUAUAUUUUGGUUAUUUUGAAUACAGACAUUGGCUCCAAAUUUUCAUCUUUGCACAAUAGUAUGACUUUUCACUAGAACUUCUCAACAUUUGGGAACUUUGCAAAUAUGAGCAUCAUAUGUGUUAAGGCUGUAUCAUUUAAUGCUAUGAGAUACAUUGUUUUCUCCCUAUGCCAAACAGGUGAACAAACGUAGUUGUUUUUUACUGAUACUAAAUGUUGGCUACCUGUGAUUUUAUAGUAUGCACAUGUCAGAAAAAGGCAAGACAAAUGGCCUCUUGUACUGAAUACUUCGGCAAACUUAUUGGGUCUUCAUUUUCUGACAGACAGGAUUUGACUCAAUAUUUGUAGAGCUUGCGUAGAAUGGAUUACAUGGUAGUGAUGCACUGGUAGAAAUGGUUUUUAGUUAUUGACUCAGAAUUCAUCUCAGGAUGAAUCUUUUAUGUCUUUUUAUUGUAAGCAUAUCUGAAUUUACUUUAUAAAGAUGGUUUUAGAAAGCUUUGUCUAAAAAUUUGGCCUAGGAAUGGUAACUUCAUUUUCAGUUGCCAAGGGGUAGAAAAAUAAUAUGUGUGUUGUUAUGUUUAUGUUAACAUAUUAUUAGGUACUAUCUAUGAAUGUAUUUAAAUAUUUUUCAUAUUCUGUGACAAGCAUUUAUAAUUUGCAACAAGUGGAGUCCAUUUAGCCCAGUGGGAAAGUCUUGGAACUCAGGUUACCCUUGAAGGAUAUGCUGGCAGCCAUCUCUUUGAUCUGUGCUUAAACUGUAAUUUAUAGACCAGCUAAAUCCCUAACUUGGAUCUGGAAUGCAUUAGUUAUGACCUUGUACCAUUCCCAGAAUUUCAGGGGCAUCGUGGGUUUGGUCUAGUGAUUGAAAACACAAGAACAGAGAGAUCCAGCUGAAAAAGAGUGAUCCUCAAUAUCCUAACUAACUGGUCCUCAACUCAAGCAGAGUUUCUUCACUCUGGCACUGUGAUCAUGAAACUUAGUAGAGGGGAUUGUGUGUAUUUUAUACAAAUUUAAUACAAUGUCUUACAUUGAUAAAAUUCUUAAAGAGCAAAACUGCAUUUUAUUUCUGCAUCCACAUUCCAAUCAUAUUAGAACUAAGAUAUUUAUCUAUGAAGAUAUAAAUGGUGCAGAGAGACUUUCAUCUGUGGAUUGCGUUGUUUCUUAGGGUUCCUAGCACUGAUGCCUGCACAAGCAUGUGAUAUGUGAAAUAAAAUGGAUUCUUCUAUAGCUAAAUGAGUUCCCUCUGGGGAGAGUUCUGGUACUGCAAUCACAAUGCCAGAUGGUGUUUAUGGGCUAUUUGUGUAAGUAAGUGGUAAGAUGCUAUGAAGUAAGUGUGUUUGUUUUCAUCUUAUGGAAACUCUUGAUGCAUGUGCUUUUGUAUGGAAUAAAUUUUGGUGCAAUAUGAUGUCAUUCAACUUUGCAUUGAAUUGAAUUUUGGUUGUAUUUAUAUGUAUUAUACCUGUCACGCUUCUAGUUGCUUCAACCAUUUUAUAACCAUUUUUGUACAUAUUUUACUUGAAAAUAUUUUAAAUGGAAAUUUAAAUAAACAUUUGAUAGUUUACAUAA